CUUCCUGGCAGAUGUCCCUCAACCCUACUGGUGCCUGGCUUCUGAGACACAGUAAGGACUUCCUUUCUCUGUAUGUCUCUGUUCUCUUUUUGAGUAUCGUCUCUUUCUCUCACUUCUCCUCCUCCCCCAAUGAGGAUGUUUCUAAAGGUUCUGUGAAUGGUAGAUUUAUAUGUUGCGAAAACUGUGCAGAUGACCCACUUUUGCCUGAGCUCCAGUUGUCCCUUUUUAUUUAUUUUCCUUCCUCUCUGCUCCUUACCUCCCCCAAAUACUGGUUGCACAGUUUCAGACACUAUUCAAGGCACUGGGGACACUGGGGAACAAGAGAGGAAAGGUCCCUGUCCUUAAGUAGCCAACAGUCUAAGAUGUUAAACACAUUGAUAAACAAGAUAAUUUCAGGUGGUGAUAAGUGCAAUAGAGAAAGUUAGCAAGGUAUGGGUAGUGAAUGCUUAGGUUGGGGGGUUGGGAGAAGGGCUCCUGGUCUGAGAAAGUGACAUUUAAAUUCAGCCCUGAAGGAUGAGUAAUGAGUAGAAGCCAGGCAGUGCAAUGAUCUGUAAGAAAAAUGUACUAGGCAGAGGGGAUAGCCAGUGCCACGCCCCUUCAGUGGGAUGAGCUUUCCAUUUCACACUGGGCUGCCUUGCUGUGUGUCCUUUGACACCUCCCAUUUAACUGCUCCAAGAUUGAUACCGUCUUUCUUUCUGACCCAUCAUCAUAAUAAUGGAUGAUUUCUCUGUUUUGGUUAAUACCGUCUCUAUCCACCACCCUGAAAACCCUAGGCCAGCAGUCUGAAAACUUUGUGAGGGGAAAGACAGUAAACAUUUUCAGCUUUGAGCACAGUACAGUCUGUCACAAGUACUGAAUCUGCUAUUGUAGCACCAAUGUAGAUAUAGACAGUAUGUAAACCAAUGAGUGUGGCUGUGCUCCAAUACAACUUUAUGUAUGGACACUGACAUUUCUAUUUUCACUUGUAACAAAAUAUUUUUCUUUUUUUUCCAACCAUUUAAAAAUGCGUCAGCUUAUUGGCGUUCAAAAUGGGCAGCGGCAGGCCAGAUUUGGCUCACAGGCCAGGAUCUGCUGCCCCCUGCCUUAGACUAACCCUGAUCUCUCCCUUUGCUUUUGCCCCACCCCACCUCCUCCCUAGGCCCUUUCAGGGCUCCCUCCCUGGUAUUCGUAUUCAGCACCUUUGCCACUCGCUGUCCCCACUGCUGCAGCCUUCCUUUGGCUUUCUUUACCUGGGUGAUCUAUCAUUGCGCACUCUAUGUCCAUGUGCAGACAUUAUUUAGCUCCCACUUUAAGUGAGCACAUGCUGUAUUUAUCUUUCCGUGUCUGACUACUGAUCACAAGCCUUUAGAAGCCCCUAUUGCCUAUAGAAAACAAUCCAAACUCCACCUUAGUCUGAUAGUAAAGGUUCCUUAUGCUAAAACCUCAGUUUAACUUUCUAGCAUACUCUCCUAUUUCUCUCCUUCUACACUGUCCCAAAAUAGAUUAUUCAUUAUUUUGCUUUCAAUGUUUCCCAUGCUUUUCUGUGUUCUUGUUCAUUUAAUGCACUUUUCCCGUGCUUCAUGCUUUCCAUCUGUCAGAAUUCCAUAGCUUUCAAGGCCCCUUCAAAUGUCCCUGGUCUCUUCCUCUGCCCCUCCCUACCCCAACAAGCGGUGUGUAUACACAUAGUCCCCUGGUGGUGUGUGAUCCUCUGUUCCAGUACGUCGUGUUCUGGUCUGUGCUUCUGUUCUUUUGCAGACACACCUCCACUAUGCAGUCACGAGGCCCUUGAGGACAGGAACCAUCUCUUUCUUCGUAAUGUCACCUUUCCCAGUAGGCACACGGCUGUUUAUUGAAUAAACACAGAUCCUGUGUACACUUGCUCAAAUUGUACAAAAUUUGCAGGAGAUUCAAAGUGGAAACAUUUUACUGAAGGGAAUUCGGUCAAAUUACAUCCUUGAUUCUUGUAUAGGUGGUACAGUUUUGUAAAGGAUCAUCAAGUAUUUUGGAAGACUCAUUGGCUCUGCCAGUGGCUUAGAUAAAUAAAUUCGGGCAAGUUAUUGAUCUCUCUCCUCAGAGAAAAAAAUUGAUGUGUUUUCUUUUAUAUAAAGAGAAAAAGAAAAAGAAAAAAUGUGAUCUGUAACUCAUUAUGUUUCCUUGCUAGAAAGCUCAAAGAUACGUUAUUUGCCUGUUUUUAGUUGCUAUCCAGUUUUCUUACAAUAAUCUCUCUGCCUCAGUCUCCUCAUCGGAUUACUUGUCACAUGUGUUAAAUCCUUCUUUUAAUUGAUGGUUCUGUUGUAUAUAUCUUUUAUAUUUAUAUAGGUAGCCUCAACUCUCCUUUUUUUGGAGAGUGGUAAUAGAAAUAUAAAUAAUAAAUAGUUGCCCUUUGGUUUCCCCAACCUGUGGUGACAACAAGAUAAUAAAACAGAUACUUAUCCUAUAUAAAACAGGCAAAAAGGCUUUGGGACAAUAUGGGAAUCAUGAUGUGGGUUUGGUGGAAAACGAGCAAAGCACCUUGUAAGGAUCUUGUAGUCUGAAGAUUAAGGUGUGCUUGGGGUAGGUCAUGUCCUCCCAGCUCUGUGGGAUUUGUAGCACAUCAUCCCACGUGGGGAGGAGAGUGGGCACGGGCAUGAGACUAUUUAUUAGCUUUUACUGUGUCAGUUGUUGGGUUAUGUAUUUUGCAUUUGAUAUUUAAUUUAAUCUUUGUAAUAGCCAGAGACUUGGAUCUUAUUGGCAUCAUUUUCCAGAUGAGCAGAGCUAAUAAAUGGCAGAACUAGAAUUCAAAUCUGAGGCUCUCUGGCAUUGAAAACAACAACAAAACAUGUUUCUACUCUUCAAAGAGACUUUUUCUCCUGGAUUGUCACUUGUCCUUUUCUUUCUCUUUCUCUCCUGACAUUGGUAUUUAAAAUGAGAACCUAGGAAACUUGUUUCUUCUAACCUAAUGUUUUUGAAGCAGUUUUAGGUCCUUGGAGAUGUGCCUUGAUGUGUCUAUACAAUAUAGUAUUUGGUAUUGUUAGAUAUAAAGAAGACCUGAGGCCGAGUGCGGUCGCUCAUGCCUAUAAUCCCAGCACAUUGGGAGGCCAAGGCAGGCAGAUCACUUGAGGUCAGGAGUUCAAGACCAGCCUGGCCAACACAGUGAAACCCCAUCUCUUCUAAAAAUACGAAAAAAAGAAAAAAAGAAAUUAGCUGGGCGUGGCAGCACGCACCUGUAAUCCCAGCUACUCAGGAGGCUGAGGCGGGAGAAUUGCAUGAACCUGGGAGGCAGAGGUUGCAGUGAGCUGAGAUGAUGCCACUUCACUCUGGCCUGGGGGACAGAGCAAGACUCUGUCUCAAAAAAAUAAAAAAAAAUUUUUUGUUUUUUAGGUUUUGGGGCAGGGCAGUUGGGUUCAUUUAGCUGUCCUAAAGUAAGUUUGGUAUAUUUUUGUGAAAUAUUUAGUUUAAAAGUUGUAUUGCUGUUUUUGACAUUUUAAGUCAGACGAGAUUUACUGUUGCUUUAUAUUACCUGACUGUUAUAUAACACGUCCUGUGUUUACCUGUGUGGGUCUGAGCGUACCAGAUGUGGUGUUAUGAAAAGCGUGCUGGACUUGGAACCAGGACGAGCCGAUGUGAGGCUGUCCUCUGCCACUUACUAGCUCUGUGACUUUGGGCUCAUAAUUGAGCCUUAUUUUUUUCUCAAUUGUAAAUGGACUGUGUAGACCUGUCACAGAGGAAGUUUUGUGAAGCUUAAAUGAGGUAGAACCUACAAAAUAGCUUCAGACAGUGCCUGGGAUCCAGCAGCAUUUAACGAAAGUUACCCACUGCUACCCCAAAUACUGAAUAUUGCCAGAAAAUCUGUAAAUGAUUACAUAAUGUUUACACCUUUAUAAGUGGUAACUUUGUAGGUAAAUAUUAUUCAAGUUAUGAACCUCUGAUUUAGGAAACCUCCUUAUGCAAAUGGUUGGCUUCCCACUACAGAAACAUCAGUAAUAAGAUAGUGGUUUAGACUCCCAAAUCUGCGACCAGUCUGUAUGUUUGAAUCCUGGCUUAUGAUCAGUCAUAGCUGAGUGAUCGUGGGCAAGUUAUUCAACCGCUUUGUGCCUCAGUUUCCUCAUCUGUAAAAGGAUAAUAGGAUAAUAAUGGCUCCUACCUUAUGGGAUUGUGAAAAUUAAAUGAGAAUGUGUGUUUAUGUAUGUGUGUGUUUGUCUGUAUUUGUACCAAUACCCUAUUGGAGUUUACCACUAUUAUUUACUGUUCCUCUUCUCUUUUCCUCCCUGUGUAAACAGCCCCAUAAGUUAUCUGGAAGUUCCCUAGUAUCUCUUUCUUAUCUUCUGUUACUGGAAGACUCCUUUUUCUUCUGUCUUUGGUCCCGUGUUAGUUGCUUCAUUUUAAUUGAGGCUAUCUUGUUCUAGUGUGCAAUACAUUCUCAUUGAUCCCUUCCCUAUACAUUUCUUGCCUAGACACUUUGAAAAAGUGUUUUUGUUUUGGGUGGAAACUGAACAUUUUCUAAUAAUGACUCAUAAACCCAGCCAGGUGUUAAGGAUACUCCUAUAUCAAGGAAAAUGAAAGCUAUACAGUCUCAAGCAAAUGAAAAAACUAUAUAAAAUGCCUAAUUGUUUAUUGAAUGUUUAUGCCAGAAAUUCAGAUCAAUAAACUGAGCCUUAGAAUGGUUGAUGUUUAAAGGUACCCGGCUUUUAAGUGGAGGAACCUAGAUUUGAUCAAAGCCAGACCAACCUGGCCCUUGGUUUCACAAUCCCUAAGCUCACUUGCCUUAAUAAGGCCUCUAGGCACCACCUCAAGACUCCAUCUGCACCCCUUAUGAACCUACACUCUGCUUUCCCUCACACUCCUGCUUUUGAGAUGGCAAAAUCACUUAUGGUUCUUUUUGGCUGCAGUAAUGUUUCCUGCUAUUUUGGCAGGGCAAAUGUAUAGCGUUUCAGAUACUUUAUGUGUUAAAUUGGCCUUUUGUGUGUUGGCUUGGAAACUUAACCACAUUUACUGCAGUGUGUCUGGGGGAAAUGUGCGCCAAGUUUCAAACAACCAACUGGGAAUGAAUUCUUUAAAAGGCAGAACUUGUGCCUGGCGCGGUGGCUCACGCCUGUAAUCCCAGCACUUUGGGAGGCCGAGGCGGGCGGAUCACGAGGUCAGGAUUCGAGACCAUCCUAGCUAACACGGUGAAACCCUGUCUCUACUAAAAAUACAAAAAAUUAGCUGGGCGUGGUGGCGGGCGCCUGUAGUCCCAGCUACUCGGGAGGCUGAGGCAGGAGAAUGGCGUGAACCCGGGAGGUGGAGCUUGCAGUGAGCAGAGAUCGAGCCACUGCACUCCAGCCUGGGCGACAGAGCGAGACUCCGUCUCAAAAAAAAAAAAAAAAAAAAAAAAAAAGGCAGAACUUGUUUAUAGCUAAGGGCUGCUGGUGUAUUUAUUUGAGUGUGUUACCUGCAUUGGUAUGCUUUAAGGGCUUCUGUGUCAUGCCUGAAGCGACAUAUUCUGGAAUGUAUACAUUAUUGCACUUCCUUGGUUAAUUGUCCUCACUGUUGCUGACCUUUGUACACUGAACCACUGCCAUUGUGUUUGGCACGUAGUAGGAACCCUGUGAAGAGACUUAUUUAGUCCUCUUUAAAGAUCAAUGGUUCUUUAUACUUUUCUGUAUGCUUGAUAUAUUUCAAUUUAAAAAAAUCAGUGGAGUAAGGAAGGAUCAGGCAACAUUGAAAGAGGAAUAUUGCCACACAGUUGCCAAUCUGAUGAAAAUACUGCUUAUGCUAGGUCGAAUUGAGACUCUGAAAGGUAUUUGGGAGCCAGACACUUAUGAGAAUACAUAUUGCUUUGAAUAUUGGAAGAAAGCAAAGCAGUCAAACGAAUUUCUUCUUGGCUUGGAGUUUUGUUUACUUUUCUCAGGUUAGAAUUGAUAGUUCUAAUGGUUUUAAGAAGUCAUGGAGAACAGGCCCACCAUGAACCUGAAUAUUUGGUUCUGAGUUUAUAGCCAUUGUCUAGUAAAUACUGUUUAAGGGUUAUUAGCACACAAUGAUCAUAAAAUCUUGUAAUACUUUUAAGAGGUGUAAGAAAUUGAAGUCACCUGAGAAUACCUCCUUCUGAUUUUACAGUGGAGAAAUAAAGGAAUCAGAGUGUUUAAGUGACUUGCCUAAGACCUGUCUGGGCCACCACUUUAGGGAUUGUUUUUUAAUCCAUCAUCAUGCUGGAUUUGUUACUGAGCGAUAAAAUGGUACAGAAGGUAGUCACAUAGAGAAUUUAGGAAAUAAAAUACUCAUUUGUUCAAAUACUUCUCAGGAGGUUGAGAUAUAUCUAUGGGUAGAAGAUUUAGAGGUUAUUUAAGAGAAAUUAGGAUUGUCUAGGGUCCACCCCUUACCGUGGGGAUUCUGAAGGGCAGUGUCUUAUGAGAGAAGAGAGAUCAAGUUACUUGGUGAGUGAGAUGUUCUAGGUGCUCAGUCCAAGGGCUGGCCGGAUGGCUAGCACUGAACUUGUGUGGAUGUUUGUUCAAACUAAUCAGCCUACGAUUGGUUUGUUCCUAAGAAUGAUAAAACUUUGUUCUAGUUUUUUAAAUUGUAAUAAUAAUUCUGUAAGCAUUUAAGAAGAAUGCUUUCUUUAAUGUUGACUUUUUUUUUUUUUUGAGACAGAGUCUUGCUCUGUCUCCCGGGCUGGAGUGCAGUGGCAUGAUCUCGGCUCACUGCAACCUCUGCCUCCGGGUUGAAGUGAUUCUGCUGCCUCAGCCUCCAGAGUAGCUGGGACUACAGGCGCCCGCCACCACGCCAGGCUAAUUUUUGUAUCUUUAGUAGAGACGGGGUUUCACCAUGUUGGCCAGGAUGGUCUCGAUCUCCUGACCUUGUGAUCCGCCCGCCUUGGCCCGCCAAAGUGCUGGGAUUGCAGGUGUAAGCCACUGCGCCCGGCCUAAUGUUGACAUUUUUUACUCCUACACGAAGCUGUUAUGUUUUUACUUAUUCUUUUCUAGUCUUUAUCGAUAAUGUAUAAAUAUGUACUGUAUUAUGUAAUUUUAAUUGCUGGAUACAUAUACCUGUCUUCUUAAACUUUUUUAUUCUAUUUUAAUAGAGUCUUUGUAAUAAUCAUUUUUGAAUGUAGUAUUUAGUUGUGUUAAUUUAUUUUAUUUUUCUUAAGUAAUCUAUGAUAGAAUAAGCUAUUUCUGUUUUUACAGAAUAUUGUAGGGAACCUUUAAAAACACACAAUUAGCAUUUUUCUGCUGCUAAUUGCUUUAUUAGGAUGAAUGCAUAGAUUUACUGUGUCAAAGGUUAUAACCAAUUUUAUGACCUUUAGUAUGUAAUUCUGGAAAAUUAAACAGAAACUUAAGUCACAAAUGGCCUUAAACAUUGGCAGGAAGCUGCUGAUUUCCUGACUGUUGUACAGGCAACCCACUGGCAAGUAACAUGUCAAAUACGGACCAUUAUAAUUCCUUAUCAUAAAGGCAGAUACAGUUUUCUUCAAAGGACAUGAAAAUAAUUUAUUUGCUUUUGAUGCCUUUUCUCACUGGGAAAUGAUAUUCUGUAAGUGCACAAUGUGCACUUGAAUGUGAAGUUGUAGUGAGGAUUUUUAUUUUUAUUUUUGUACAACUGGGUUAUAAUAAAGGAAACAAACUUUAUGUCACUUCUAGGCUGAUGAAAUACCCUAGUAAAUGCAGUACAUUUUUGCAUGACUAAUAGGAGUAGGGGCGGGGCUUUGACUUUUACAUCAGUCAGGUUAAAAUCACCUGUUUGCUGGUUUCCCUAAGACAGUGAUGUAUUGCCCUUUGCUUAACUUUUUGUUAGUUGGGAAAUGUAUUCUACUUUGAUGACUGGUGUUUUUCUGCUUAGUGGGGAUAUUUUCUGUGAAGCCAGGAUAAACAAUUCUAUAAUGCAAAUCUGAACACAUCACUGCCUUGCUUAAAAUCUUUCACUAGCUGCCCUUUGCUGUUAGGAUUAAGUCUAUCCAAACUCCUUAGCAUGGUAUGAAGAGCCUCUCAUGGUCACAGCCUUCCUUUCCUUCCAUUCCCUUUCUUGCAGUCAGCACUCCAGCCCUUCUGACCGUUUUUGUUUCUUAAAUAUAUUGUGAUCUCUCUUACUUCUAGGACAGUAAGUUCUGUAGAUUCCUUGGUGAAUAUACAGCCUUAGAGACUGCAAGAAUUCUGAGCAGUAUUUCUAAGGGUUAGAUUUCCCUCCAAGUACCAUUAACAUUCUGGGCUGCCACAUUUCAAGAUUUACUCUGGAGAUGUGAGGUGGAAGCCAUGUUAAAUGGCUGGAAGAUAGUCCUGUGGGAGAGAUAAGCUUUAUCAUUUUAUUUUUACCAGGUGUGUUGCAGUGAGUGUUGAAAAGCCUUCCACAAAAAAUAGAGUCUUCUUUUUUCCCCUGUUAUGAUUAAAUUACUGGCUGCUAAUCUUUCAUGAUGAAGAGAGAAGCCCAAAAGCAAUUUCAGAACAUGGAUCUCAUGCUGAUUAGUGGUUAUAAUGAUUUCACAUGGAUAGUAUUCCUUGUGUUUGAAAGUUAUUUUAUUGGUGAGAUCUGCGAAAUCAACAAGGCUAGUUUAUCUUUGCAAAAACUUGUGACAAGCUUAUAGCUACACUCCUUGGGGAACACAGUUCACAUUUAAGAUUUUGCCUCAGGCACCUCUGUUCAGCUUUAUGCUGUGUCUUUCAGAUUCUAGAUAUGAAACUGGUUUGACAUUAAUACCUAGCAUGAUAGCUUUUUAGAUACACUCUUUGCUUGCAUUAAGUCAGACAAAAUCUGCAGAGCCUAGCACUAUGCUCAGUAUAUGAGCUGCUUUGUCUGUGUAUCUUGGUUCAUACGAGAGUCAGUAUACCUAGGCAGUCAGUAAACAGUCAUUGAUUAGAUUUGGAUUUAAUAAAUUUAAGCCUGGCCAAUAAUUAGUGGGAACCAAACCAAGGCAACCUAUAGUAAAUGGAGCAUUGCAUCGAAGAUCUCAGUUCUUCAAAUAAGGCACAGAUAAAGGAUCUCUAUGUAUUACCCUCCUGUUCUUGGAUUUAAUUGUUCAAAUGUUUCACCCAAAACCUCAAUUUCAGGCUAAUAUUUAGGCAUUCUCUUCUAUGUUAUACCUCAGGUAAUUUGGAAACAUUUGUAUUUCUAAAUCUAUUUCUGUAUAAACUUUCUAUGAAUUGUAUAUCUCUCCCUCUCUAUAUUAUAUAGUAUAGAUUUAAAUUGAAAAAUUCAUUGUUCCCUUCAGAGGUAUAAGAGUAUUCUGGCCCAGCUGGAAAUGUUAUGUUAAAUUUGAAAUUCUACUACCUAAAUUUUGGACUUGUGUACUACUGUUUUAGUAGAGCUAUAUGAUACUGCAGAUAAAGUUCCAAAACAAUCUGUGGUGAAAAAAUUCUUGUUCAGGGACCUGUUGUUCAGUGAAACUGCUUUUCUGUUGGGUACCUGUAUUCUUUUUUGGUUAAGUUAAAAAAAAAAAAGGAUUUAUUGGCCUAUGUCUUAAGGGGGUUGGGGGAGGACCCAUGGUUCAUGGACUCCAAGGAUAUAAAGGCAUUCCCCUUCUCAGUAAGAAUCCUGCUAUUCUGCUUCCUGUUCAUUGGUCUUAUGUUCUGCCACAAUGAGGUUUUAUCCACAUGAUUUGAAUAGAGAACAGUUGGCUGCUCCAAGAUGAUGUCUGUUUAUCAAAUCUCCCUGAAAGACUUGUGUUUGUGUCACCCUUGGUCUGGAAGGUGGACAGUGCAGGCAUGGAUGGGGGUCAGGUGGGACACUGUGAUCUGUAGUGUUAACAGAAUCACCUGGUAUGAGAAGUUUCUAGAGAGAUAAAAACAGAUGUCAGCUGUAAUAUAUUGAACUGGCAGUUAAAAAAUUUUUUUUAAGUUGUGGAAAAUAAACAACAUAAAAUUUACCAUGUGAGCCAUUUUUAAGCUUACAGUUCAGUAGUGUUAAGUACAUUCACGUUGUUUUACAUCUAAUCUCCAGAACUCUUUUCAUCUUGCAAAACUGAAACUCUGUACCCAGUAGAUAAUAACUACCCAUUGCUUUUUCCUGCUAGCUCCUGCCAACUACCAUUCUACUUUUUCUAUCUAUGGAUUUGACUACUCUGGCUACUUCUUAUAAGUGGAAUUGUCCAUAAUGUCCUUUUUCACUAGCAUGUUUCACUUAGCAUAAUGUCCUCAAGGUUUAUCCAUGUUUUUGCAUAUGAUGGAAUUUCCUUCCUUUUAAAGGCUGAAUAAUAUUCCAUUGUAUGUAUAUACAACAUUUUGUUUAUCCAUCUAUGUUGUUGGAUGCUUGGGUGGCUUCUACCUUUUGACUGUUGUGAAUGAUAUUUCUAUGAACAUGGGUUUGCAAAUAUCUCGUUGAGACCCUGCUUUCAGUUGUUUUGUGAACUGCCACUUUUUUGGAUAACUCUCAUUUGAAACUAUGUUCAUCUUUUUUUCCUUAAAAACUGCCCGUAAUUAACUCUUUUUGGUGCCCAGUAAGUGGAAAAUUCAGAACAGCAAAAUGUUUGCUUUAUUCAACAAACACCUUCUCAAAAUCUAGAAAACAAAGAACAUUAGAGAACACUGUGGAAGUAAGUAUGAUUGUGGGUAGCUGGCUGACGUAGAAGAUUUUAAUUUUUACUAUGAUGCAUAAAUAUGUACCUUUGCAAGUUUUAGCAGACAAGAGCAUGAGGUCCGAUCAUAGACCUAUGACUUUGGGGAAGUUACCUAAAGCCUUGCCAGCCACCAUUUACUUAUUUGCAGAGAGGGGGUUGGUUAUACCUGCUAGGGUUAAUUAGACUAUUAAAUGAGAUAACAUGUGCAGAACACAUAGCCAGUGGUAGGUGGUCAGUAAGUGGUUUCCUCUCUCCUGUAUUCUUCCAGGGGAAUAGAAGACGACCACUGUGUGAGGAUCUCUGUAUUGUUCAGCUCUGAUGCUCCUCCUACUGUGGGUGGUAGAUCUCCCUCUUAACAAGGCUUUCUUGGCAAGCAUUUUUAAACUUUACAUUUUCUUAUUUUUUUAUUAUUGUUAUUGAUAUUUUGUUUGGCAUAGGUACUGUAUUGACAUGGUUCAGAAAGCAAACCAGGGCCGGGUGCCGUGGCUCAUGCCUGUAAUCCCAGCACACUGGAAGGCCGAGGUGGGUGGAUCACUUGAGGUCAGGAGUUAAAGACCAGCUGGCCAACAUGGUGAAACCUUAUCCCUACUAAAAAUACAAAAAUUAGCUGGGCGUGGUGGCAGGCGCCUGUACUCAGGAGUAUCCCAGCUACUCAGGAGGCUGAGGCCAGAGGAUGGCUUGAACCCUGGAGGUGGAGGUUGUAGUGAGCUGAGAUCACACCACUGCACUCCAGCCUGGGCGACAGAGCAAGACUCUGUGUCAAAGAAAAAAAAAAAGAAAGCAAACCAGUAUAACAGGGUACAAAUUGAGAAGGUUUGCUCCCAUUUUUGUUUGUCCGUCAACUUCGUUCCCUGUUUCCUUAAGUGCUCUUCUCAUCUCUAGGACCUAUUAAUCGCUUCUCUGAAGUAGCUUUGGAAAGUAGAGAAGAAAAUCCAGUUUGCUUCUUGGAGAACACUGGACAGCUGAAUAAAUGCAGUAUCUAAAUAUAAAAGAGGACUGCAAUGCCAUGGCUUUCUGUGCUAAAAUGAGGAGCUCCAAGAAGACUGAGGUGAACCUGGAGGCCCCUGAGCCAGGGGUGGAAGUGAUCUUCUAUCUGUCGGACAGGGAGCCCCUCCGGCUGGGCAGUGGAGAGUACACAGCAGAGGAACUGUGCAUCAGGGCUGCACAGGCAUGCCGUAUCUCUCCUCUUUGUCACAACCUCUUUGCCCUGUAUGACGAGAACACCAAGCUCUGGUAUGCUCCAAAUCGCACCAUCACCGUUGAUGACAAGAUGUCCCUCCGGCUCCACUACCGGAUGAGGUUCUAUUUCACCAAUUGGCAUGGAACCAACGACAAUGAGCAGUCAGUGUGGCGUCAUUCUCCAAAGAAGCAGAAAAAUGGCUACGAGAAAAAAAAGAUUCCAGAUGCAACCCCUCUCCUUGAUGCCAGCUCACUGGAGUAUCUGUUUGCUCAGGGACAGUAUGAUUUGGUGAAAUGCCUGGCUCCUAUUCGAGACCCCAAGACCGAGCAGGAUGGACAUGAUAUUGAGAACGAGUGUCUAGGGAUGGCUGUCCUGGCCAUCUCACACUAUGCCAUGAUGAAGAAGAUGCAGUUGCCAGAACUGCCCAAGGACAUCAGCUACAAGCGAUAUAUUCCAGAAACAUUGAAUAAGUCCAUCAGACAGAGGAACCUUCUCACCAGGAUGCGGAUAAAUAAUGUUUUCAAGGAUUUCCUAAAGGAAUUUAACAACAAGACCAUUUGUGACAGCAGCGUGUCCACGCAUGACCUGAAGGUGAAAUACUUGGCUACCUUGGAAACUUUGACAAAACAUUACGGUGCUGAAAUAUUUGAGACUUCCAUGUUACUGAUUUCAUCAGAAAAUGAGAUGAAUUGGUUUCAUUCGAAUGACGGUGGAAACGUUCUCUACUACGAAGUGAUGGUGACUGGGAAUCUUGGAAUCCAGUGGAGGCAUAAACCAAAUGUUGUUUCUGUUGAAAAGGAAAAAAAUAAACUGAAGCGGAAAAAACUGGAAAAUAAACACAAGAAGGAUGAGGAGAAAAACAAGAUCCGGGAAGAGUGGAACAAUUUUUCUUACUUCCCUGAAAUCACUCACAUUGUAAUAAAGGAGUCUGUGGUCAGCAUUAACAAGCAGGACAACAAGAAAAUGGAACUGAAGCUCUCUUCCCACGAGGAGGCCUUGUCCUUUGUGUCCCUGGUAGAUGGCUACUUCCGGCUCACAGCAGAUGCCCAUCAUUACCUCUGCACCGACGUGGCCCCCCCGUUGAUCGUCCACAACAUACAGAAUGGCUGUCAUGGUCCAAUCUGUACAGAAUACGCCAUCAAUAAAUUGCGGCAAGAAGGAAGCGAGGAGGGGAUGUACGUGCUGAGGUGGAGCUGCACCGACUUUGACAACAUCCUCAUGACCGUCACCUGCUUUGAGAAGUCUGAGCAGGUGCAGGGUGCCCAGAAGCAGUUCAAGAACUUUCAGAUCGAGGUGCAGAAGGGCCGCUACAGUCUGCACGGUUCGGACCGCAGCUUCCCCAGCUUGGGAGACCUCAUGAGCCACCUCAAGAAGCAGAUCCUGCGCACGGAUAACAUCAGCUUCAUGCUAAAACGCUGCUGCCAGCCCAAGCCCCGAGAAAUCUCCAACCUGCUGGUGGCUACUAAGAAAGCCCAGGAGUGGCAGCCCGUCUACCCCAUGAGCCAGCUGAGUUUCGAUCGGAUCCUCAAGAAGGAUCUGGUGCAGGGCGAGCACCUUGGGAGAGGCACGAGAACACACAUCUAUUCUGGGACCCUGAUGGAUUACAAGGAUGACGAAGGAACUUCUGAAGAGAAGAAGAUAAAAGUGAUCCUCAAAGUCUUAGACCCCAGCCACAGGGAUAUUUCCCUGGCCUUCUUCGAGGCAGCCAGCAUGAUGAGACAGGUCUCCCACAAACACAUCGUGUACCUCUAUGGCGUCUGUGUCCGCGACGUGGAGAAUAUCAUGGUGGAAGAGUUUGUGGAAGGGGGUCCUCUGGAUCUCUUCAUGCACCGGAAAAGCGAUGUCCUUACCACACCAUGGAAAUUCAAAGUUGCCAAACAGCUGGCCAGUGCCCUGAGCUACUUGGAGGAUAAAGACCUGGUCCAUGGAAAUGUGUGUACUAAAAACCUCCUCCUGGCCCGUGAGGGCAUCGACAGUGAGUGUGGCCCAUUCAUCAAGCUCAGUGACCCCGGCAUCCCCAUUACGGUGCUGUCUAGGCAAGAAUGCAUUGAACGAAUCCCAUGGAUUGCUCCUGAGUGUGUUGAGGACUCCAAGAACCUGAGUGUGGCUGCUGACAAGUGGAGCUUUGGAACCACGCUCUGGGAAAUCUGCUACAAUGGCGAGAUCCCCUUGAAAGACAAGACGCUGAUUGAGAAAGAGAGAUUCUAUGAAAGCCGGUGCAGGCCAGUGACACCAUCAUGUAAGGAGCUGGCUGACCUCAUGACCCGCUGCAUGAACUAUGACCCCAAUCAGAGGCCUUUCUUCCGAGCCAUCAUGAGAGACAUUAAUAAGCUUGAAGAGCAGAAUCCAGAUAUUGUUUCAGAAAAAAAACCAGCAACUGAAGUGGACCCCACACAUUUUGAAAAGCGCUUCCUAAAGAGGAUCCGUGACUUGGGAGAGGGCCACUUUGGGAAGGUUGAGCUCUGCAGGUAUGACCCCGAAGGGGACAAUACAGGGGAGCAGGUGGCUGUUAAAUCUCUGAAGCCUGAGAGUGGAGGUAACCACAUAGCUGAUCUGAAAAAGGAAAUCGAGAUCUUAAGGAACCUCUAUCAUGAGAACAUUGUGAAGUACAAAGGAAUCUGCACAGAAGACGGAGGAAAUGGUAUUAAGCUCAUCAUGGAAUUUCUGCCUUCGGGAAGCCUUAAGGAAUAUCUUCCAAAGAAUAAGAACAAAAUAAACCUCAAACAGCAGCUAAAAUAUGCCGUUCAGAUUUGUAAGGGGAUGGACUAUUUGGGUUCUCGGCAAUACGUUCACCGGGACUUGGCAGCAAGAAAUGUCCUUGUUGAGAGUGAACACCAAGUGAAAAUUGGAGACUUCGGUUUAACCAAAGCAAUUGAAACCGAUAAGGAGUAUUACACCGUCAAGGAUGACCGGGACAGCCCUGUGUUUUGGUAUGCUCCAGAAUGUUUAAUGCAAUCUAAAUUUUAUAUUGCCUCUGACGUCUGGUCUUUUGGAGUCACUCUGCAUGAGCUGCUGACUUACUGUGAUUCAGAUUCUAGUCCCAUGGCUUUGUUCCUGAAAAUGAUAGGCCCAACCCAUGGCCAGAUGACAGUCACAAGACUUGUGAAUACGUUAAAAGAAGGAAAACGCCUGCCGUGCCCACCUAACUGUCCAGAUGAGGUUUAUCAACUUAUGAGGAAAUGCUGGGAAUUCCAACCAUCCAAUCGGACAAGCUUUCAGAACCUUAUUGAAGGAUUUGAAGCACUUUUAAAAUAAGAAGCAUGAAUAACAUUUAAAUUCCACAGAUUAUCAAGUCCUUCUCCUGCAACAAAUGCCCAAGUCAUUUUUUAAAAAUUUCUAAUGAAAGAAGUUUGUGUUCUGUCCAAAAAGUCACUGAACUCAUACUUCAGUACAUAUACAUGUAUAAGGCACACUGUAGUGCUUAAUAUGUGUAAGGACUUCCUCUUUAAAUUUGGUACCAGUAACUUAGUGACACAUAAUGACAACCAAAAUAUUUGAAAGCACUUAAGCACUCCUCCUUGUGGAAAGAAUAUACCACCAUUUCAUCUGGCUAGUUCACCAUCACAACUGCAUUACCAAAAGGGGAUUUUUGAAAACGAGGAGUUGACCAAAAUAAUAUCUGAAGAUGAUUGCUUUUCCCUGCUGCCAGCUGAUCUGAAAUGUUUUGCUGGCACAUUAAUCAUAGAUAAAGAAAGAUUGAUGGACUUAGCCCUCAAAUUUCAGUAUCUAUACAGUACUAGACCAUGCAUUCUUAAAAUAUUAGAUACCAGGUAGUAUAUAUUGUUUCUGUACAAAAAUGACUGUAUUCUCUCACCAGUAGGACUUAAACUUUGUUUCUCCAGUGGCUUAGCUCCUGUUCCUUUGGGUGAUCACUAGCACCCAUUUUUGAGAAAGCUGGUUCUACAUGGGGGGAUAGCUGUGGAAUAGAUAAUUUGCUGCAUGUUAAUUCUCAAGAACUAAGCCUGUGCCAGUGCUUUCCUAAGCAGUAUACCUUUAAUCAGAACUCAUUCCCAGAACCUGGAUGCUAUUACACAUGCUUUUAAGAAACGUCAAUGUAUAUCCUUUUAUAACUCUACCACUUUGGGGCAAGCUAUUCCAGCACUGGUUUUGAAUGCUGUAUGCAACCAGUCUGAAUACCACAUACGCUGCACUGUUCUUAGAGGGUUUCCAUACUUACCACCGAUCUACAAGGGUUGAUCCCUGUUUUUACCAUCAAUCAUCACCCUGUGGUGCAACACUUGAAAGACCCGGCUAGAGGCACUAUGGACUUCAGGAUCCACUAGACAGUUUUCAGUUUGCUUGGAGGUAGCUGGGUAAUCAAAAAUGUUUAGUCAUUGAUUCAAUGUGAACGAUUACGGUCUUUAUGACCAAGAGUCUGAAAAUCUUUUUGUUAUGCUGUUUAGUAUUCGUUUGAUAUUGUUACUUUUCACCUGUUGAGCCCAAAUUCAGGAUUGGUUCAGUGGCAGCAAUGAAGUUGCCAUUUAAAUUUGUUCAUAGCCUACAUCACCAAGGUCUCUGUGUCAAACCUGUGGCCACUCUAUAUGCACUUUGUUUACUCUUUAUACAAAUAAAUAUACUAAAGACUUUA